CUGGGAGUCCAUGCGUGCCUGGAGCAGCAGCGUCUCCAGGGACAGGCAGCCACCAUGAGCCUCAGUGAGGAGCAGGCCCGGAGCUUUCUGGACCAGAACCCCGAUUUUGCCCGCCAGUACUUUGGGAAGAAACUGAGCCCUGAGAAUGUGGCCGCGGCCUGCGAGGACGGGUGCCCGCCGGACUGCGACAGCCUCCGGGACCUCUGCCAGGUGGAGGAGAGCACGGCGCUGCUGGAGCUGGUGCAGGAUAUGCAGGAGAGCAUCAACAUGGAGCGCGUGGUCUUCAAGGUCCUGCGGCGCCUCUGCACCCUCCUGCAGGCCGACCGCUGCAGCCUCUUCAUGUACCGCCAGCGCAACGGCGUGGCCGAGCUGGCCACCAGGCUUUUCAGCGUGCAGCCGGACAGCGUCCUGGAGGACUGCCUGGUGCCCCCCGACUCCGAGAUCGUCUUCCCACUGGACAUCGGGGUCGUGGGCCACGUGGCUCAGACCAAAAAGAUGGUGAACGUCGAGGACGUGGCCGAGUGCCCUCACUUCAGCUCAUUUGCUGACGAGCUCACUGACUACAAGACAAAGAAUAUGCUGGCCACACCCAUCAUGAAUGGCAAAGACGUCGUGGCGGUGAUCAUGGCAGUGAACAAGCUCAACGGCCCAUUCUUCACCAGCGAAGACGAAGAUGUGUUCUUGAAGUACCUGAAUUUUGCCACGUUGUACCUGAAGAUCUAUCACCUGAGCUACCUCCACAACUGCGAGACGCGCCGCGGCCAGGUGCUGCUGUGGUCGGCCAACAAGGUGUUUGAGGAGCUGACGGACAUCGAGAGGCAGUUCCACAAGGCCUUCUACACGGUGCGGGCCUACCUCAACUGCGAGCGGUACUCCGUGGGCCUCCUGGACAUGACCAAGGAGAAGGAAUUUUUUGACGUGUGGUCUGUGCUGAUGGGAGAGUCCCAGCCGUACUCGGGCCCACGCACGCCUGAUGGCCGGGAAAUUGUCUUCUACAAAGUGAUCGACUACGUCCUCCACGGCAAGGAGGAGAUCAAGGUCAUUCCCACACCCUCAGCCGAUCACUGGGCCCUGGCCAGCGGCCUUCCAAGCUACGUGGCAGAAAGCGGCUUUAUUUGUAACAUCAUGAAUGCUUCCGCUGACGAAAUGUUCAAAUUUCAGGAAGGGGCCCUGGACGACUCCGGGUGGCUCAUCAAGAAUGUGCUGUCCAUGCCCAUCGUCAACAAGAAGGAGGAGAUUGUGGGAGUCGCCACAUUUUACAACAGGAAAGACGGGAAGCCCUUUGACGAACAGGACGAGGUUCUCAUGGAGUCCCUGACACAGUUCCUGGGCUGGUCAGUGAUGAACACCGACACCUACGACAAGAUGAACAAGCUGGAGAACCGCAAGGACAUCGCACAGGACAUGGUCCUUUACCACGUGAAGUGCGACAGGGACGAGAUCCAGCUCAUCCUGCCAACCAGAGCGCGCCUGGGGAAGGAGCCUGCUGACUGCGAUGAGGACGAGCUGGGCGAAAUCCUGAAGGAGGAGCUGCCAGGGCCCACCACAUUUGACAUCUACGAAUUCCACUUCUCUGACCUGGAGUGCACCGAACUGGACCUGGUCAAAUGUGGCAUCCAGAUGUACUACGAGCUGGGCGUGGUCCGAAAGUUCCAGAUCCCCCAGGAGGUCCUGGUGCGGUUCCUGUUCUCCAUCAGCAAAGGGUACCGGAGAAUCACCUACCACAACUGGCGCCACGGCUUCAACGUGGCCCAGACGAUGUUCACGCUGCUCAUGACCGGCAAACUGAAGAGCUACUACACGGACCUGGAGGCCUUCGCCAUGGUGACAGCCGGCCUGUGCCAUGACAUCGACCACCGCGGCACCAACAACCUGUACCAGAUGAAGUCCCAGAACCCCUUGGCUAAGCUCCACGGCUCCUCGAUUUUGGAGCGGCACCACCUGGAGUUUGGGAAGUUCCUGCUCUCGGAGGAGACCCUGAACAUCUACCAGAACCUGAACCGGCGGCAGCACGAGCACGUGAUCCACCUGAUGGACAUCGCCAUCAUCGCCACGGACCUGGCCCUGUACUUCAAGUGCGCGCCUUCCGGGAGGGGGCGCCUCGCGGGGCGGGCGGGUAGCCUGGGACCCCCGGCAGACACGGGGGCGCAGCGGCGGCACAGCCCGGGGGACGCAGCCCCGGAUUCCGUCCCUGCCCGCCGGCCCCGCGCACCCCGGAUGGGGCCUCGCUCGGGCUCCGCGCCUCCCUGCAGACGGGCGCUUGGGGCGGGGUCUCCACACUUGCUCCCACCUGCACCUCCCUUGUUCCCUGGGUUCAGGAAGAGAGCGAUGUUUCAGAAGAUCGUGGAUGAGUCCAAGAACUACCAGGACAAGAAGAGCUGGGUGGAGUACCUGUCCCUGGAGACGACCCGGAAGGAGAUCGUCAUGGCCAUGAUGAUGACAGCCUGCGACCUGUCUGCCAUCACCAAGCCCUGGGAAGUCCAGAGCAAGGUCGCACUUCUCGUGGCUGCUGAGUUCUGGGAGCAAGGUGACUUGGAAAGGACAGUCUUGGAUCAGCAGCCCAUUCCUAUGAUGGACCGGAACAAGGCGGCCGAGCUCCCCAAGCUGCAAGUGGGCUUCAUCGACUUCGUGUGCACAUUCGUGUACAAGGAGUUCUCUCGUUUCCACGAAGAGAUCCUGCCCAUGUUCGACCGACUGCAGAACAAUAGGAAAGAGUGGAAGGCGCUGGCUGAUGAGUAUGAGGCCAAAGUGAAGGCUCUGGAGGAGAAGGAGGAGGAGGAGAGGGUGGCAGCCAAGAAAGUAGGCACAGAAAUUUGCAAUGGCGGCCCAGCACCCAAGUCUUCAACCUGCUGUAUCCUGUGAGCACUGGUCCCAUGGGGACCCUAUGGCUCCCUCAAUCUUCACCCACUAGGAUUUGGGUUCUGCCUGUGGCUAUUUGCUACAAGAGGUUAGGAAGCCCAAGAAAAUGACUGAAGAUCAUUCUGGAUAUUUUAAUUUUUUUUUUUUUUUUUUUUUGAGAUGGAGUCUUGCUCUGUCACCCAGGCUGGAGUGCCGUGGCACGAUCUCAGCUCACUGCAACCUCCACCUCCCAGGUUCAAGCGAUUCUCGUGCCUCAGCCUCCUGAGUAGCUGGGACUACAGGCGCCCACCACCACACAUGGCUAAUUUUUGUAUUUUCAGUACAGAUGGGGUUUCACCAUAUUGGGCAGGCUGGUCUCGAACUCCUGACCUCAGGUGAUCACCCGCCUCAGCUUCCUGAAGUGCUGGGAUUACAGGCAUGAGCCACCACGCCCAGCCUGUUUUUAUAAACUGAAGCCAACUGUGAAUAAACUGUAGCCUACAUUACUCAUCCAUUUUUGGAUAGUUACCACUGGGAGACCUUUGAAAAGGGUCCAUGAACUCUGAAAUCACUGAGAACAUUUGCAGCCACACAUGUACAUAUGUGUACACAGGUAGACAGAUGGACACAGGCCGUUUCUCAUCCAGUUUAGGAAAACACACAUGCUCAGGAAUUCAGAAUAAAAUAAACAGAAAACUA